GCAGUGCAUCCUGGGUUGGCGUAGCCAUGGCGUCUCGUGUCCUUUCAGCCUAUGUCAGCCGCCUGCCCGCGGCCUUUGCGCCGCUGCCCCGGGUCCGGAUGCUGGCCGUGGCCCGGCCUCUCAGCACCGCUCUCUGCUCCGCGGGGACCCAGACGAGGCUCGGGACUUUGCAGCCGGCCUUAGUGCUCGCGCAGGUGACUCGUGGUGACUUUGCUGCCGCUUGGCAAGGAGAUCCAGUUAGAAGGAGCAGCAAGACCUUCCAGGAGGCCAUGCUGGAAGGACAUGGGGUUCCUGGUAGAGUUACACAGUUGUGCCGCCAGUAUAGCGACAUGCCUCCUUUGACGUUAGAGGGCAUCCAGGACCGUGUUCUUUACGUAUUGAAACUCUAUGACAAGAUUGACCCAGAGAAGCUUUCAGUAAAUUCUCAUUUUAUGAAAGACCUGGGCUUAGACAGUUUGGACCAAGUGGAGAUUAUCAUGGCCAUGGAAGACGAAUUUGGGUUUGAAAUUCCUGAUAUAGAUGCUGAAAAGUUAAUGUGUCCACAAGAAAUUGUAGAUUACAUUGCAGAUAAGAAGGAUGUAUAUGAAUAAAGUAUCAGACCCUUUGGCUUUGCUGAGAGAGGACUCAGAUGAUAGUGACGAAUGUCUGGCAGUGAGGACACAUUUUGGCAUUCUUGCUGACUCUGACAGAGUGAUUCUGAUGGACUUGUAUUUAAAUUGUAUGUGUUUUACUCUUUGAAAAUAAAUCUAUAAAACCAA